GAGAAGAGCCGGGCAGGCGAGAGGAGCGGAGCGGCGGCGGCGGCCGGAGAGGGAGCGGCGGGCGCAGGCGGCGGCGGCGGGCGCGGCGUUGGCGGCGGCCCCGGCGGAGCGAGCGCGGAGCCGGAGAGCCGGGAGCACAGGCGGCCGCGCCGCGUCCUGGCCCGGCCCGGGCCCGCGCGCCAGCAUCGUCCGCAGCGCGGGCAUCCGGACCCUCCGGGCGCCCGGGGGGCUCCAGCAGGCGCGGGGGAACGGGAGGGGGCCUGCGUGCGCCGGCGGGUGCUCUCCAGGGGGCGUCCCGGCGAGGCCCAGAGCGGGCCGGGGGCGGCGGCGGCUGGAGGAGCCCCCCCCACCUCCGGUCGGGCGCCCGGCUCAGCCGCCGGCGACGCGAGGCGCUCGCGGGGAUUUGCAACUCGCCGGAUCGAGUCCUCGCCGGCGGGGCCGCUGCUGCUGGGGAAGCUGCUGCUGGUGGCCACAGGCUGGCACCAGGGCCCUGGACUUUAGAAGCCGUUGCUGCCCUCUCUGUCACCUGAAGCGGGGCCCUCUCCCAUCCCACCCUUGCCCCGCCUCCCUGCCCCCACCGGGCCGGCCCUGCCCGCCGCCGGACCCUGGCAUGUCAAGACCUGGUCCGCGCCUGCCUGCCCAGCCCGCGGAACCCCGGCGGCCCCGCGAGCUAGGAUGAGGGGCCAGGCCGCCGCCCCGGGCCCCGUCUGGAUCCUCGCCCCGCUGCUACUGCUGCUGCUGCUGCUGGGACGCCGCGCGCGGGCGGCCGCCGGAGCAGACGCGGGGCCCGGGCCCGAGCCGUGCGCCACGCUGGUGCAGGGAAAGUUCUUCGGCUACUUCUCCGCGGCCGCCGUGUUCCCGGCCAACGCCUCGCGCUGCUCCUGGACGCUACGCAACCCGGACCCGCGGCGCUACACUCUCUACAUGAAGGUGGCCAAGGCGCCCGUGCCCUGCAGCGGCCCCGGCCGCGUGCGCACCUACCAGUUCGACUCCUUCCUCGAGUCCACGCGCACCUACCUGGGCGUGGAGAGCUUCGACGAGGUGCUGCGGCUCUGCGACCCCUCCGCACCCCUGGCCUUCCUGCAGGCCAGCAAGCAGUUCCUGCAGAUGCGGCGCCAGCAGCCGCCCCAGCACGACGGGCUCCGGCCCCGGGCCGGGCCGCCGGGCCCCACCGACGACUUCUCCGUGGAGUACCUGGUGGUGGGGAACCGCAACCCCAGCCGUGCCGCCUGCCAGAUGCUGUGCCGCUGGCUGGACGCGUGUCUGGCCGGUAGUCGCAGCUCGCACCCCUGCGGGAUCAUGCAGACCCCCUGCGCCUGCCUGGGCGGCGAGGCGGGCGGCCCUGCCGCGGGACCCCUGGCCCCCCGCGGGGAUGUCUGCUUGAGAGAUGCGGUGGCUGGUGGCCCUGAAAACUGCCUCACCAGCCUGACCCAGGACCGGGGCGGGCACGGCGCCACAGGCGGCUGGAAGCUGUGGUCCCUGUGGGGCGAAUGCACGCGGGACUGCGGGGGAGGCCUCCAGACGCGGACGCGCACCUGCCUGCCCGCGCCGGGCGUGGAGGGCGGCGGCUGCGAGGGGGUGCUGGAGGAGGGUCGCCAGUGCAACCGCGAGGCCUGCGGCCCCGCUGGGCGCACCAGCUCCCGGAGCCAGUCCCUGCGGUCCACAGAUGCCCGGCGGCGCGAGGAGCUGGGGGACGAGCUGCAGCAGUUUGGGUUCCCAGCCCCCCAGACCGGUGACCCAGCAGCCGAGGAGUGGUCCCCGUGGAGCGUGUGCUCCAGCACCUGCGGCGAGGGCUGGCAGACCCGCACGCGCUUCUGCGUGUCCUCCUCCUACAGCACGCAGUGCAGCGGACCCCUGCGCGAGCAGCGGCUGUGCAACAACUCUGCCGUGUGCCCAGUGCAUGGUGCCUGGGAUGAGUGGUCGCCCUGGAGCCUCUGCUCCAGCACCUGUGGCCGUGGCUUUCGGGAUCGCACGCGCACCUGCAGGCCCCCCCAGUUUGGGGGCAACCCCUGUGAGGGCCCUGAGAAGCAAACCAAGUUCUGCAACAUUGCCCUGUGCCCUGGCCGGGCAGUGGAUGGAAACUGGAAUGAGUGGUCGAGCUGGAGCGCCUGCUCCGCCAGCUGCUCCCAGGGCCGACAGCAGCGCACGCGUGAAUGCAACGGGCCUUCCUACGGGGGUGCGGAGUGCCAGGGCCACUGGGUGGAGACCCGAGACUGCUUCCUGCAGCAGUGCCCAGUGGAUGGCAAGUGGCAGGCCUGGGCGUCAUGGGGCAGUUGCAGCGUCACGUGUGGGGCUGGCAGCCAGCGACGGGAGCGUGUCUGCUCUGGGCCCUUCUUCGGGGGAGCAGCCUGCCAGGGCCCCCAGGAUGAGUACCGGCAGUGCGGCACCCAGCGGUGUCCCGAGCCCCAUGAGAUCUGUGAUGAGGACAACUUUGGUGCUGUGAUCUGGAAGGAGACCCCAGCGGGAGAGGUGGCUGCUGUCCGGUGUCCCCGCAACGCCACAGGACUCAUCCUGCGACGGUGUGAGCUGGACGAGGAAGGCAUCGCCUACUGGGAGCCCCCCACCUACAUCCGCUGUGUUUCCAUUGACUACAGAAACAUCCAGAUGAUGACCCGGGAGCACCUGGCCAAGGCUCAGCGAGGGCUGCCUGGGGAGGGGGUCUCGGAGGUCAUCCAGACACUGGUGGAGAUCUCUCAGGACGGGACCAGCUACAGUGGGGACCUGCUGUCCACCAUCGAUGUCCUGAGGAACAUGACAGAGAUUUUCCGGAGAGCGUACUACAGCCCCACCCCUGGGGACGUACAGAACUUUGUCCAGAUCCUUAGCAACCUGUUGGCAGAGGAGAAUCGGGACAAGUGGGAGGAGGCCCAGCUGGCGGGCCCCAACGCCAAGGAGCUGUUCCGGCUGGUGGAGGACUUUGUGGACGUCAUCGGCUUCCGCAUGAAGGACCUGAGGGAUGCAUACCAGGUGACAGACAACCUGGUUCUCAGCAUCCAUAAGCUCCCAGCCAGCGGAGCCACUGACAUCAGCUUCCCCAUGAAGGGCUGGCGGGCCACGGGUGACUGGGCCAAGGUGCCAGAGGACAGGGUCACUGUGUCCAAGAGUGUCUUCUCCACGGGGCUGACAGAGGCCGAUGAAGCAUCCGUGUUUGUGGUGGGCACCGUGCUCUACAGGAACCUGGGCAGCUUCCUGGCCCUGCAGAGGAACACGACCGUCCUGAAUUCUAAGGUGAUCUCCGUGACUGUGAAACCCCCGCCUCGCUCCCUGCGCACACCCUUGGAGAUCGAGUUUGCCCACAUGUAUAAUGGCACCACCAACCAGACCUGUAUCCUGUGGGAUGAGACGGAUGUACCCUCCUCCUCCGCCCCCCCGCAGCUCGGGCCCUGGUCGUGGCGCGGCUGCCGCACGGUGCCCCUCGACGCCCUCCGGACGCGCUGCCUCUGUGACCGGCUCUCCACCUUCGCCAUCUUAGCCCAGCUCAGCGCCGACGCGAACAUGGAGAAGGCGACUCUGCCGUCGGUGACGCUCAUCGUGGGCUGUGGCGUGUCCUCUCUCACCCUGCUCAUGCUGGUCAUCAUCUACGUGUCCGUGUGGAGGUACAUUCGCUCAGAGCGUUCUGUCAUCCUCAUCAACUUCUGCCUGUCCAUCAUCUCCUCCAAUGCCCUCAUCCUCAUCGGGCAGACCCAGACCCGCAACAAGGUGGUGUGCACGCUGGUGGCCGCCUUCCUGCACUUCUUCUUCCUGUCCUCCUUCUGCUGGGUGCUCACCGAGGCCUGGCAGUCCUACAUGGCGGUGACGGGCCACCUCCGGAACCGCCUCAUCCGCAAGCGCUUCCUCUGCCUGGGCUGGGGGCUCCCUGCACUGGUUGUGGCCAUUUCUGUGGGAUUCACCAAGGCCAAAGGGUACAGCACCAUGAACUACUGCUGGCUCUCCCUGGAGGGGGGACUGCUCUAUGCCUUCGUGGGACCUGCCGCUGCCGUUGUGCUGGUGAACAUGGUCAUUGGGAUCCUGGUGUUCAACAAGCUCGUGUCCAAAGACGGCAUCACGGACAAGAAGCUGAAGGAGCGGGCAGGUCAGCCGUCCCCGCACCCCCUCGGGCGCGCCCUCAAGUGUGCCGAGUGUGGAGUCCUCUCUGCCGCCGAUGCCACCUCCGACGCCACCAGUAACGCCAUGGCCUCCCUGUGGAGCUCCUGCGUGGUGCUGCCGCUGCUGGCGCUGACCUGGAUGUCGGCUGUGCUCGCCGUCACCGACCGCCGCUCCGCCCUCUUCCAGAUCCUCUUCGCUGUCUUCGACUCGCUGGAGGGCUUCGUCAUCGUCAUGGUGCACUGUAUCCUCCGUAGAGAGGUCCAGGACGCUGUGAAAUGCCGUGUGGUUGACCGGCAGGAGGAGGGCAACGGGGACUCAGGGGGCUCCUUCCAGAACGGCCACGCCCAGCUCAUGACCGACUUCGAGAAGGACGUGGAUCUGGCCUGUAGAUCAGGUCCUGAGGCAGUGACAGGCAGUGGCUUUCUGAGCUGUGGAGAGGCCAAUGGACCAUGCUCCCUCUGGUCAUUUAGAUAUUUGAAGAGCACCUUCUCUAGAGACAGCCCUGGCAGAGGAGCUGGGACAGCCCCAGUGCUGAACAAGGACAUCGCGGCCUGCCGCACUGCCACCAUCACGGGCACACUGAAGCGGCCGUCUCUGCCCGAGGAGGAGAAGCUGAAGCUGGCCCAUGCCAAGGGGCCGCCCACCAAUUUCAACAGCCUGCCGGCCAACGUGUCCAAGCUGCACCUGCACGGCUCACCCCGCUAUCCCGGCGGGCCCCUGCCCGACUUCCCCAACCACUCACUGACCCUCAAGAGGGACAAGGCGCCCAAGUCCUCCUUCGUCGGUGACGGGGACAUCUUCAAGAAGCUGGACUCGGAGCUGAGCCGGGCCCAGGAGAAGGCUCUGGACACGAGCUACGUGAUCCUGCCCACGGCCACGGCCACGCUGCGGCCCAAGCCCAAGGAGGAGCCCAAGUACAGCAUCCACAUUGACCAGAUGCCGCAGACCCGCCUCAUCCACCUCAGCACGGCCCCCGAGGCCAGCCUCCCCGCCCGCAGCCCGCCCUCCCGCCAGCCCCCCAGCGGCGGGCCCCCCGAGGCACCCCCUGCCCAGCCCCCACCGCCUCCGCCCCCACCGCCACCACCUCCCCAGCAGCCCCUGCCCCCACCGCCCAAUCUGGAGCCGGCACCCCCCAGCCUGGGGGAUCCCGGGGAGCCUGCCGCCCAUCCGGGACCCAGCACGGGGCCCAGCACCAAGAACGAGAAUGUCGCCACCUUGUCUGUGAGCUCCCUGGAGCGGCGGAAGUCGCGGUAUGCAGAACUGGACUUUGAGAAGAUCAUGCACACCCGGAAGCGGCACCAAGACAUGUUCCAGGACCUGAACCGGAAGCUGCAGCACGCAGCGGAGAAGGACAAGGAGGUGCUGGGGCCGGACAGCAAGCAGCCGGAAAAGCAGCAGACGCCCAACAAGAGGCCCUGGGAGAGCCUCCGGAAAGCCCACGGGACGCCCACGUGGGUGAAGAAGGAGCUGGAGCCGCUGCAGCCGUCGCCGCUGGAGCUUCGCAGCGUGGAGUGGGAGAGGUCGGGCGCCACGAUCCCGCUGGUGGGCCAGGACAUCAUCGACCUCCAGACCGAGGUCUGAGCGGGUGGGCGGCGGCCACGCACUGGGCCACGGAGGAGGGAUGCUGCUCCGCCCGCUCCUGCCGCAGACGGGCACAGACACGCUCGCGGGCAGCGGGCCAGGCCCGCACCCCGGCCUCAGGGCGCUCAGACGGCGGCCAGGCACAGGGCCCGCAGUGCUGGGACCAGAGCCAGAUGCAGGACAGGAGGCGGCCCGGCCAGCGGGCACAGGGCACCAGAGGCCGAAGGUGCCUCAGACUCCGCCCUCCUCGGGCCGAGGCCCAGCGGGCAGAUGGGCGGACGGCUGUGGACCGUGGACAGGCCCAGCGCGGCCAGCGUCCCAGGGUACCCGCCUGAGCUCCUGCUGCGGAGGAGCUGCCUGCUUGGCCCGGCCGGCCUGGCACCGUUUUUUAAACACCCCCAUCCCUCGGGAAGCAGCCAGCUCCCCACACCUUCCAGGGCCCUAGGCCCCUCCUAGACCCAGGUGGAGGGCACAGCCCUCCGACCCUCAUGGCCCCCAGGGGCAGGACUGAGUCCCCUCCAGGAAGAAGCAGGGGGGAAUCUAUUUUUUCUCUCCUUUUCUUUUCUUCAAUAAAAAGAAUUAAAAACCCA